AGUCUGCCCCGCGCGCGGAGCUGCGCGCACUGGGUCCCCAAGAGCCCGCGGGCGUCCGGCAGCCGAGCGCACGUUCUUUCGGAUGCACACGCCCGGGUCCCUGGCGUCUGACGCCGUGGGGAGGGCAGCGAGGCCCCAGGUGAGUGUGUCUGCCUGCGCGGGGCUGGGGAGGCGCCGCUGGGCAGAUGUGCGCCCUUGCUGUGCGCCUUUGGAAGCAGGACUAAUCAGUGAGCGGAGAGCGGGCGGGGAUGUCCGUGUGGAGUUUCCCUUGGCGUCCCCAAGUUACUGCGUGUUGCAGUGAGAUGUGGCUCUGCAAGGCAGGACAGGCUUGUGGACGGAGGCGGGGGCGUUUGGCCCGGAAAGCCGGUGUUGACAGACACCAGGUGCGACACGAGGAGUAGUAGUUGAGGGUAAGAGCAAAUCCCGGCACUCUCCAGGUGCAGCGGCAAACAUGGGCAGGCUGGAGCACUCUCCUCAAAGAGGACCACAAGCAGGCUCCUCCCUCAACCUCGGACUGAUGGGGGCACAACUCCGCGCCGGCUGUGCCGCCGGGUUCUGCAGAGGUCUGAGGCUGGAAGGGGGUAUGCGCCGCUUUGGGCAGGAGUCCUUUGAACCAUUCGCUCUGGACACCUUUUACCUUUCGUGAAGGUGGAGCUCACUUCAGGGUGCUUUGCUUUUUUCCCCUGUAAUUAGUAUUCUGCUGAUCUGGUUCAUCUGCAUCCUGCGUCCCCUCCGCCUGGCAGUACCUUAAGUGUGCGCUGGGAAAAGGGCGCCCUGCUUCUCUGAAUGCAUGGUGGACUUCUUCAUGGGUGCACAUGGUACACUGCUACUUGCCGGUAUUCAACCUUCCAGUGUGGAUUAAUGAGAAAAGACCCGUUAUUCUGUACCGCUUCACGUUUUAGAUCGUUAACCCUACGGAUUUCUUAAAUGUCAUAGUUCAGGUACUUACUACACCAUUCUUUGGCGAAGGCUAUUCAGCAGUGGUGACCUCUUCCAAUCCAACACUCUACAGAUUAUUAUCUCUGGACUCCCAGCUGACACCCUGCCGGAGGCAAGAGCUACUAAGCCAACUGGAACUGUGCCUUUUCUCUUGUCAAGGUUUUUUUCUUACACAGGAAAAAGAAAGAAAAAAAAAAGAUGAAGUUGGGCAAAGUGGAGUUCUGCCAUUUUCUGCAGCUAAUAGCUCUUUUCCUGUGUUUUUCUGGGAUGAGUCAAGCAGAACUCUCAAGGUCCAGAUCAAAGCCCUAUUUCCAAUCAGGGAGGUCCCGGACCAAGCGCAGCUGGGUGUGGAAUCAGUUCUUUGUGCUGGAGGAAUACAUGGGUUCAGACCCCCUCUAUGUAGGAAAGCUUCACUCUGAUGUUGAUAAAGGAGAUGGUUCCAUCAAAUACAUCUUGUCAGGCGAAGGGGCAAGUUCCAUUUUCAUUAUUGAUGAGAACACUGGGGAUAUUCAUGCCACCAAGAGACUGGAUCGUGAGGAGCAGGCCUACUACACGCUCCGAGCUCAAGCGCUGGAUAGGCUCACCAACAAACCCGUGGAGCCCGAGUCGGAGUUUGUCAUCAAAAUUCAGGAUAUCAACGACAAUGAACCCAAAUUUUUGGAUGGCCCAUACACGGCAGGAGUUCCCGAAAUGUCUCCCGUGGGGACCUCAGUGGUACAAGUGACAGCGACGGAUGCUGAUGAUCCUACAUAUGGCAACAGUGCCAGAGUGGUCUACAGUAUUCUGCAAGGACAGCCGUACUUCUCAGUGGAGCCAAAGACAGGAGUCAUCAAGACUGCCCUUCCAAACAUGGAUAGAGAGGCUAAAGACCAGUAUUUGCUUGUCAUUCAGGCAAAGGAUAUGGUUGGUCAAAAUGGAGGACUGUCAGGAACUACAUCAGUCACUGUGACCCUAACUGAUGUCAACGAUAAUCCACCUCGCUUUCCUCGAAGGUCUUAUCAAUAUAACGUCCCAGAGUCAUUACCUGUAGCCUCAGUUGUGGCCAGAAUUAAAGCUGCUGAUGCAGAUAUUGGAGCUAAUGCUGAAAUGGAGUACAAGAUUGUGGAUGGUGAUGGUUUGGGCAUUUUUAAGAUUUCUGUUGACAAAGAAACCCAGGAAGGAAUCAUUACUAUACAGAAGGAGCUGGAUUUUGAAGCCAAAACAAGUUACACGCUACGGAUAGAAGCUGCAAAUAAAGAUGCCGACCCUCGCUUUCUGAGCUUGGGUCCGUUCAGUGACACGACAACUGUGAAGAUAAUUGUGGAAGAUGUAGAUGAGCCCCCUGUGUUCUCUUCACCCUUGUACCCUAUGGAGGUGUCGGAAGCUACCCAGGUUGGGAAUAUCAUUGGCACUGUAGCAGCUCAUGACCCAGAUUCUUCCAAUAGCCCUGUGAGGUACUCAAUUGACAGAAACACAGACUUGGAGAGAUACUUCAAUAUUGAUGCCAACAGUGGGGUCAUCACAACUGCCAAGUCUUUGGAUCGAGAGACAAAUGCUAUUCACAAUAUCACAGUCCUUGCAAUGGAGAGCCAGAAUCCAUCUCAAGUAGGAAGAGGCUAUGUGGCCAUCACUAUACUUGACAUCAAUGAUAACGCCCCUGAAUUUGCCAUGGACUAUGAGACCACCGUCUGUGAAAAUGCCCAGCCGGGGCAGGUUAUCCAGAAAAUCAGUGCUGUGGAUAAAGAUGAGCCAUCCAAUGGACACCAGUUUUACUUCAGCUUAACAACGGAUGCAACAAAUAACCACAACUUUUCAUUGAAAGAUAACAAAGACAACACAGCCUCAAUACUGACCAGGAGAAACGGCUUCCGGAGACAGGAACAAUCAGUUUACUAUCUGCCAAUUUUCAUUGUGGACAGUGGAUCUCCCUCACUUAGCAGCACCAACACCCUCACCAUCCGCGUGUGUGACUGUGAUGCUGACGGCGUAGCCCAGACCUGCAAUGCAGAGGCCUAUGUCCUACCUGCUGGCCUCAGUACAGGAGCCCUGAUAGCCAUACUCGCCUGUGUCUUGACAUUAUUGGUGUUGAUCCUCCUUAUCGUCACUAUGAGAAGACGGAAAAAAGAGCCCCUUAUUUUUGACGAAGAAAGAGACAUCAGAGAAAAUAUUGUGAGAUACGAUGACGAGGGCGGGGGAGAGGAGGACACGGAAGCGUUUGACAUGGCUGCACUGAGAAACCUCAACGUCAUCCGAGACACCAAGACCCGGAGGGAUGUGACUCCAGAAAUUCAAUUCCUGAGUCGACCAGCUUUUAAAAGCAUCCCAGAUAAUGUCAUCUUUAGGGAAUUUAUUUGGGAAAGAUUAAAAGAAGCCGAUGUUGAUCCUGGUGCUCCUCCUUAUGACUCCCUGCAGACAUAUGCUUUUGAAGGAAAUGGCUCAGUUGCUGAAUCACUCAGCUCUUUAGAUUCCAUCAGCUCAAACUCUGAUCAGAACUAUGACUACCUAAGUGACUGGGGACCUCGCUUUAAACGACUCGCGGACAUGUAUGGGACUGGCCAAGAGAGUUUGUACUCAUAGCCUUGGAACCUUAAUUCGAAAUGUACUGAAGAAAAAGUAACAGCAAAAAAUAAAAUAAAAUGAAAUAAAAUAAUAAACCACUACAUACAGAAAACAAGAACUCCCCUUGCUGGAGACAGAUGGUUGUAAAUAUUUCUCCAUUUUUAAUUGUUUAGAUUUCUGCCUUGGUGAGGCAUAUCUUCAUUAGACUUAUCUAAAGGACUGCACUGACCACAGACUCUGAGCAUUUGAAGGUUUUUUGAUAAAAAUAAAUGCUCAGUGGUUUGUGAAUAGAUAGCAACUCUCAUAUACCUGCAAAGGCACCAAACCUCUAUGAGAAAGUAGUGCCCUGUGUUGUCAGUGAGUCAAAGAUGCCCUGUACAUACCUUCAUGGUACUGUCAUUGAGAGGAAUAGAACAUGAUGAGCUAUUGAAAAACCCUGGAACUUGUUGCAUAUCAAAACUUGGGACAAAUUUAAUUUACAGAGAUGCUUAUAGCUUACUAUAUUAUAGAAUCCAACAGAAUUAUGUUGCUCUUGAUUAACAGAAAUAUUUUAUUUAGGAAUAUAUAAAUUCCCAGAAAUUCCUUCCUAACUGAAAACCCUACCACAAAAGCCAGUAAAAUUUAGUUUAAGGCAAUAUAAACCAUUGUUUAUCCAAUAAAUUAUGAAGUGUUCCAAAUAAGAAAAAGGUAAAUAAUUUGAUAGUUUUGAGAUGCUUGUGUAGGUAUGAUAAAAAAAAAAGUUGCUGUCUGUUCAUUGAUUUUUAUUAUCUCUUCUGAUUUGUACAGGAGAAUAUCUUUUCUUUUUUAUUUGACACAUGGUGUUGUAUUUAUUUUGGAGCUCCAAUCUCCACUAAAUUCAGGUCCAUCAUACUGCCUCAUAGUAUUAAACUCAUCAGAACAUGCUGAUUUUUCUCCAGCCCGAGCUACAUGAAGGAAAUGAAGCAUGGAAAUGGAGAACUAAUAGUAAAGCAAUUGAGCCCUGUUGCAGGUCACAUCUCAAAGAGGAGCACAGCUACAAGGACAUAUAAAUUGUUCUUCUGAGCCAUUAGAAUGUCAAAACAUUGGAAUAAAAUAUUUGUAUUUUAGAAAGACUUCAGAGAGAAUUGAGAUUUUCUUUGAUGCAAGAAUUAUUUUUCAAGAUCAUGAGUUCUACAUGCUCCAAAGACGAUUUCAAGAACACAACCUUUCUUGCUGCAAACCUAUUGAGUAAAAUAUUGAGUUUUUAAAAGUCUUAAUAUAAUGUUAUAAAAAUUAAAAUCCAUCUUUAAAUUCUGAUGCAAAUAUGUCCCUCAAGAAUUAACCAAGCAAUGUAUGAUUUCUGUGUGGUUUAGAUGUGCCAAAGGAAGGAAGGCAAUUGCAAGUCAUCAUGUGUUUAAGUUUGAGUUGAGCUUGUUAGAGUAUGACUUUCAUGACCAAAAUGAUGUUUCUACCUAUUAUUUUUCCUAGAUUAAUACUAGUUUAAUGUGCAUAUACAUUCAAGUAAGAAUGGAUUUAUUUUUUCCUUCCUUUCUCCUUUUAAAAAUAAUUCAUUGUUGGGUUCCUAAUACAUUUACAGAUAGUAAACACUGUGUAGAGAAUCAUGUUCUAAAAGUGCUUUUUGAAAGGUAGACAGUGGAAUUAGAAUAUUAAUAUGUUGAUUACACAAAGAAGAACUAUGUAGGAUUCUGUAAACUUGCAGCCCAACUUUAGAAAUGAAGUAUGUAAAAGUGGCCUUCAACUUCAUAAGUAUAAAUAAUCCAAUAAAUUUCAUUACCUGCAAACAGUUCUUUAAUUUGAAUAGAGUUUUGUAGACAUUGUUUUAUGACUAUAUAGAUAUGCUUCUUGCUGUAUUAAUAUGCAUAUAUAUUUUAAAAAAUUAUAACAGUGAAAGAUACUGUUCAUAACUUUUAAUCACACAUGCAAGUUUUUCAAACUAAAAAAUAACAAACAAACAAAAAAACACGCGUAUUUACCCAGUUCAAUAAAAUCAGAGUGUGGUGCAGGAAUUACAGAGUUGUUAAGUCAGCAAGGUGCUGAGAAAACAGUUUGUAAUAAUCCCCUUGUUGUCUGCAAGAAGAUGAAAUAGUUUAGUACAUUUGGAUGAUGUCAAAACUGCUGAUUGUUGCACAUACCACUAAACGGAGGUGUGGAUGUAUUUUAGAAAAGGAACACACAUCAUUCACCCUGCUUUUUCUGCUUUUAAAAUGUGUGUUUUUUCUCAUUAAUUUUUUCAAAUGGUUACCAAUGAUAGAUUGGAAAAAGAAAGGUUCAUGUUUAAAUAAUAAUUUAAAAUUAUUGCAUAUACCCAAUUGCUAUUUAUGUGUGGAUGAUUAUAUGAAUACAGUAUUACAUUUCAUUCAGUGGUAUUUUUUAAUUAAAAAAAUUAAUUUAAAAAAUUAAUUUUUGAGAUGGCUGGAAGAAUGUUCCUAAUAUAGGUAGUAUUUAUAUGAAGUAUUCUAAGCUUAAUUGUAAUAGUAGUAAAUUUUUUGCCGUUGCUUAUUUUAGUUUUCUUUUUUCUUCUGAAAUCUAAUGCUAUAUAUGAUGACUGUCAAUACUUGAGAUAUAGGCUUUGUUUUAAAAACAGUGAUUGAAGAGCUGAUUGAUAAAAUUAAUAUUAAGUCUAGUUGGAAAAUUCUCCAAAUAUGAUUUAAAUAAAUAUAUAUUAUCAAGUUGCUUAAAUUCAGUAUUAUACUGAAACCAACUAGAAUGAGCUCACAGGAACUAAUUCUUCAUAUCUCUUCCCAACUCCAGGUACAGUGAUAUCAUUUUGGUAGGUUGAUGUCAGCCUUGGUGGGAUUAUUUAGACCACAACAGUAAUCAGCAAACACUACCCUUUUCUCUGGAGAACAAGUUGUUAAACAUUUACCAGCACUCUACUGCUUAAAUUAUUUUAUAAAAUGAAAUGUCAUAAUUGUAAAUAUAGUAUGAAUUUAUAUGAUUUAAAAUAAUGACAUGAAAGGAAUUUAUGCUAUAUUUUACUACUAAAUAACAAUGUAUGUGGUAGUGAUUUCCUGAAGUGAAAUCCUUGGAGCUACUUGUAGACAGGGAGAGGAGUCACUUCUUUAUGGAAAACAAUGGCUAAAUUUCAAGUAGAGAUAAUAGUUCAGGAAGUCAAUAUAUUUAAUUAUUUUCCACUUGUCCAUACAGGAGCAUCAAUAGAAACUCAGGGUUUGCCAAAUUAUGCCCAUUUUGAACAGUUUAAUUUAUUGAAAAAUCAGAUGCAUUUUACUUCUUACUGUCUAUGUCAAGGAAAUACACCCAAGCCCUUAAUCUGAAUUGUCACCAUUGCAUUAUUAAAAAUCAACAUAAAAAUAUAAAAAUCAAAUCUUAAGGAAAUGGAUUUCUGGAGAUCAAGCCUAAAUUAUCAAUCUCAAUUCACAAAUUAGUCUCUGAAAGAAAUAUUCCAAGAUCAGCCAGCUAAGGAACAAAAUCAGGAAAGAGACAUCAAUAAAAAAUUAGGUAGUAAUUUGCAGGCAAUAAGUAGAUUUUUGAUUUUUCUACAAGCAAUCACCAGAUCUGGGAUCUGGUAAAUGUCUUUAUUUGCCAGGAAGCUCUGCUGAUGACUACAAUUGAGGUUAGUUGUCUACAAGAUACAUGCAGGAGGUAGUAGUGGUUAAGUAAUGGUAGCUGCCUUUUCACUCUGCCCUCUGAGGAAGUUUUAAAUUAUUUUAUCUUCAUGCACAAUUACAUUUACUACAUUGGAUGGUAGACAUAGGCAAUUAUUUUCAUGUCAACGGCAUAGUUACACAAUGUAGGAAUGAUAUUUGUGAAGUGAUCCACAUGCCCAAGAAAUGCAAAUGCAAAUAGUGUUGUUAGCAUUUAUAUUGAAAUAUAAAAUCUAAAGCAGCUUAAAAUAAGCUAAGCUAAACAAACUGCAAGAAGCUAAAUGAUUUAAACAUGUUAAAGUUUUAAAGCACUAGCUGUAAAUAUUAAUCUUCAGAUUUUCAAUUUAACAUGUAUUCACUUACAAACUGUUCUAAUAAUAACACUAAUUAUUUUCCAAGUCACCAUUUAAAGUUUUAUUUACAGUUGACCUAAUCCAAUUGAAGUUGAUGAAAGCUUCAACUUAUUUUUUAACUCUUUCUGGUCCACGAUGCCUGGAGGCAAGUGAAAUAUAUAUGACAAAUAAUAGAUAAACCAAUUUAUUUUCUGUUAGUGUAUGUUUAUUUUUUAAUUAUUAAUAAUGUAUAUUGUGUGUAUAUAUGACGGUGUAUGAAAGUUGGCAAUGAAAGCUAAUACAAUCAUGUUAGUCGGCUGGAUAUAAUAAAGAACAAGAAAGGAAUAAUAGCAUUUGCAUUUUAAAUGUAAUUGAAACUAUUUCAGAAGAGUGGGAUAAGCCCUUAAGAAAAAUGGGAGAUGUUUAAGGCUGUGAUUUGGCCGACAUUGUAACGUAUAAUUCUGUGGGAAAUUUUUCAAGCAAAUCAAGACAGGCAGUGUGCGUUGCAUUCUGACACUUUUUCAUUGUUAUGCUAACUUCUACUGGCUUAGAAUGUAACUGAAAAGGAUGUGUGCCUGUGUUUUUUUUUUUUUUUUUUUUUUUGACGUGGAGUCUCGCUCUGUCGCCCAGGCUGGAGUGCAGUGGUGCGAUCUCGGCUCACUGCAAGCUCCGCCUCCAGGGUUCACACCGUUCUCCUGCCUCAACCUCCGGAGUAGCUGGGACUACAGGCGCCCGCCACCGCGCCCCGCUAAUUUUUUUGUAUUUUUAGUACAGACGGGGUUUCACCGUGGUCUCGAUCUCCUGACCUCGUGAUUCGCCCGCCUCGGCCUCCCAAAGUGCUGGGAUUACAGGCGUGAGCCACCGCGCCCGGCCCUGUGUGUGCGUUUUCAUGUGUGUGAUUGGGAACCUUGAGAGAUGUAUCUGAAGUAAUGUAAAAAUAAGAGUCUCAUAAUUCCUGGUUAAUGCUGGCGUAUUGUUGUCACCUGCCAAGUGACUGUUAGGCAAUAAGACUAGAAAAUAUGGUACCGAAUGAAAGGAGAAAUAUCUUAUUUGCUGUAACAAUCUAAUUUAUAUUAAGGUAAGGAUUUUGGUGGCUAAGGAAAGAACAUUUAGCUGUUAUUUGUGUAAUUGUCACAUAUUAUUGUGCAGAUUUAAUCUCAUUGUUAACAGAAUAUAGAGUGUGAAUUAUUUGUUAUUAAAUGUUACUGGGCUUUGGUGUCAGUGUGGUAUACCAGAAAUUACCUCUGGUCUGUGGUUAUAAAAUCUAGGUCAGAAGCUCAGUUUCGCCACAUUUUUGCUGUGCCCUAGAUGCCAUUUUCAUUCUCUGAACUUUUAUAGCUUCAUGAUUAAAAUUGAGUUAAUUACUAUUGUGUUUCAGAGGCUUGUGAAUGAUUAAGUGAAAGACUGUGUAAACAGUAAAACACUAUAAAAAGAUAAAGCUUUAUUAUGGGAAAUAAUGGGAAUUAUAUAAAAAGGUUGAUAAUUGUUAUAUGGUAAACAGAGAAUUUCUGUUUGGAGAUACAUACAUUAAGGAAAAAUAUAUGCAACUUGGUAUCCUAAAUUGGAAAAUAAUAUUCAAAUAGAUAAUUGUCAUAAUUAAUUGAAGCCACUCAAAUACAGUUAUUUAUAAGAUCUCAGAAGAUUGCAGUUUAACUCAACAUAAUUCAACCAUUCAUAUGAAUUAAUGAUAUCCAUAUGUGAAUGGGAUUAUAAAUAAAGAACAAAUCUUUCUUACUUAUAAUGAUAACUGAGUGGAAGAUAAAGGACUGCCUUUAGAUGAUCCCAGCCUCAUUGAUGAACACAAAACACCAGAAUAGAGAAAAAGACAAUAAUGAGUAUAAGUUAAGUGGUCUUCCAGGCAUCCAGAGUAGAUAAAGAAAAUGAAGUUCUAGAGAAUACAAUACUUUUUAAAGUCACAGUGACAUAUGUGUAAUUAAUAAUUUAUACACUUGAAAAAAUUAGAUGCAAUGAUAUUGACUUAACAUGAAAACCAUCCUGAAUGCAAUGCACUCUUGAUGACUCAAACUCACUUAUAUCUUACAACAGCUCAUCUUAAUCUCUUACGAAUGAAGAAACUCUAGGAAACUAAAAAAUAAUAUAUAAUGGAUAUUACUUUUUGUCAGUGAUGCCAAGAUGAAUGUUAAUAAGCUCUCUUCUCAACUUUAGCUCUUAGUUAUCUGGUUAUUUUAUGCUCAUGUGAACAGACACUAGAAACAAAUAUAUUAAUAACUAUGUAACUAAUGAGAAUGUUGAAAGUACAGCAUACUUUCAUUCAAAAACAAACUUGCAUUUUCAUUUUAUUAAUGAAUAUAAUGAUGUUAAUGGUUUAUAUAAGCAGGAAAAACUUAUAUGAUUCACUACCCUACAGCUUCAUGUUCUAAUUUUGUGAGUAUAAACCCUAUGUUUUUGUAUAUCAAGAUCUGGAAUAUGUUGUAUACUGUAUAUGACCAAUACUUUAAGAACAAUCAAGUUUUUUUAUUAUUAUUAUUAUACUUUAAGUUUUAGGGUACAUGUGCACAAUGUGCAGGUUAGUUACAUAUGUAUACAUGUGCCAUGCUGGUGUGCGGCACCCAUUAACUCGUCAUUUAGCAUUAGGUAUAUCUCCUAAUUCUAUCCCUCCCCCCUCCCCCUACCCCACAACAGUCCCUAGAGUGUGGUGUUCCCCUUCCUGUGUAACUAUAUAGCAAUUUCAUUUUACAUGCAGUAAUUUUAAAUGCCCAAAAAUAAAAGGAAAAGGAAAAAUAAGUCACUACACAACUUAUAUAUAUUAUGUAUUUGUCUUUGAAUUUUGUGUGCGUAUGUGUGUGUGUAUAUAUAGACAGCAUGCGCACACAUACAUACACGUGUGCAGGAACACACACAAUUUGAGGCGAAAUGUUGAAGUAAAGUAAAUGACUUUUAAAUAUUUUCUUUUUAGCUUUUAAGAUGUCUAUUAGAUCCAACCUCUACAAUUAAAUUAUAUGAGCAUACUGAGGGAGAAUUGCACAUUUGUAAAGUUUCUCUUUAGUAGAGAUUUCAGAAUUUUUUUUCUCAAAUUUAGAGGAACGAACAAUUCACAUUAGUAAAACACACAGCAUUACUUUCAAUGAAACUAUAAUUUUUAUGUUUAUGAGAUUCCAUUAUAAUUACAUUAAAAAGAAAACCACUUUUAUAAUAUUUUUGCUUAUGUAAGAGUCACUUCUAUAGUAAAAGAGCCUUAAAAAUGUUAAUUCAAUUGACUGCAGAAUUGAUCCUGAAAAUCCAGUUCAUUUAACCUUGGAAAUGAGACAUGAAGCAUAAAACCUGGGGUCAGGAUGUAUGUCCAAACUGAAUAGAUUAUUUUCGUUCAGCUCAAGUGCUAUCUUUCAGGCAAAUAGACUCCUACAAUAUUCAGUAUUGGAGAUGUUUAAAACAAAUAUAAGAAAGAGUACUGUUUCAGAACUAACCAGCGAAGAGAUGUAUACAAAGUGUACUCUGAAUUGGAAUAAGUGUAGGAAGACAAGCCGUGAGAAUGUGAGACCUCAGUAUAUUGCUGUGUUUUAUUGUGUGUUUUGCUGUAUUUUUAAAAAAUAAGAAAAAAUUAUCACAGAGUAAGAUACAUAGAAGAAAAUAAUUUCCGCAAUUCUUGGUACCUCAAAAGACCUGACACACUACAAUGAAGACUUCUGUUGUCAUCAUUCUCAGCUGUGAUGGUGGCGCCAUCCUGGUUUCCAGCUUAUACCUCCUGACAACUCGGUACAGAAAAUGAGUAUCAUUGUAAUUAAAGUUUGAUAUUUUCUUCUAAGUGACUGAUUUUUAAUAUAAAAGUAUCACAAUAAAGUUUUUCCACAGAUAUGUAAUUUUAAGUUAGAUAACAUUCUAACAUAUACAUGGUUUCAAUUUUCUUAUAAGUCUGUGAAUCACUCAAGUUAGGCAUUGUUAGGUUUUUUAAGGAAAAACUUUGAUGCCCAGAAUAACUGUAACUUAUGCAAACACACACACACACACACACACUCACACACACACGAAGUAAAUGGUAGAAAUGAAAGAAGAAGAAGAAGAAAAAAACAUUGGGACAUUUUGCCCUUUAUCUUUUUAUUAAGACUGUCAAUAAAUGAUGGUUUGGUUUAAGAGGAUAAGAAGAUAGCUGAAACUCUAAUAAUUGGACUUUCCAAUCUUAAUUAUGCUUUAGUUCCCUUACCAGGAUUAGGAAACUUCUUUGUGAUUCUUUUUUAAAAAUAAUUUAAUCAGGAAGUGACAUUAAAUUCUGUUUCAAUGUAAUGAGAAAAUAGAAAUAUUUAUAUUGUCAUUACGAUGGCACUUCACCAGUAUGUCCUAAUCUAUUCUCUAUUACGUCUCUGAGGUGGGACAUUGUUGUGAGAAUGGACGAGAGCACAAAAACACGGCAGACCAGAUUUUCUGAGGGUUACCCGCUAUGCAGAUUCAUAAACUUGUUAUUGAAUAGUUGGCACACAAGGGUAGGAGAAAAAUCCCAACAACCCUUCCACCUUUUCCAAAAAGAAAAAAAAGAAAGAAAAAGCUAAAUCUUAUGAAGCUAAACUGUCAACAAACAGUUCCACUGAAGUUGCCAUAGGGACAGCUCCAACCCAGUGCUGGGCUCGUGGAAGGCAGCAAGGUACCUGCAUCAAGCCAAGAUCCAUGAAAGUGCUAAUGUCAUUUGAGGCCAGUUUCACCCCUACCUCCCAUAAAUCAUUUUAAACCAAAUAUGAAUUAGUAGUCAAAAAUGACCAAACACAGACGAUAACCCACCAUGAAGGAGAUGGUUCAUAGAAAUCUCCAAGAACUUCAGAUAAUUCAGGUAAUUAUCAGAAACAUGACAAGAAAAAGCUUUGUGUAAAAUACAGAAUACAACACAAGGAAUAAUGAAAAGAUGAUCUAUGAUGGUGUAUACUUGCAAAAUAACUAAAGAGUGUAUUUAAGAUUUAAAUAUAUCUUUGAAGCUAGAAGUACUAUGGAGAUUGUAUAUACUAUAUUAGACACUGUGCAAGAAGGAACUUGUGAAGCUAAAAAAUAGAAUGCAAUAAAUUAGCUAGUCUGCCACAUAGAGAAAAAAAGAUAAUCUGCAAGAACAUAAGGGACAAGGAUAAAAUACGGAGUUUAACGUGCUUAUAACCAGUGUGAUCCUUGUUAAUCAGAAUUCUAGAAUGUUCCAUUGCCUUAUGUGACACCUCCACUGCCCCCACUUUUUCUUUUUUUUUGACAAGGUCUCAUUAUGUUUCCCAGGCUGGCUUUUAACUCCUGGCCUCAAGUUAUCCUCCUGCCUCUGCCUCCUUAAAUACUGGAAUUACAGGUGUGAGUCACCAUGCCAGGUGUCUCCCAUUUUUUAAUGGUAGCUUAACUUCACCUGAAGCCUCCUAUGCCACUAUCUUUAUAGGAAGCUUUACCGACUUUGUACGACUUGGUUUAAUUUAUUCAGCUUAAUGGUCCAUUUAACCAAUAUUGUUAUAAAUUUAUGAAGCUUCAAUUCUAGCAAAAAUAAACUAUGUGCACUCAUCAAAAUGUGUGGCACACCUAUGAAAAGUGAUCAGGAUGCCCAAGCAAUUUUAAUUAAAAUCAGAUAAUUAAA